AGACACAAGAACAACUGAAAAGAAUAAAGCAGAUGUGUGAGUUACUAUUCCUUACAGCAAAAGAACCUCAUCAGAACCGCAGGCUGGAAAGAGUCUAGCUGUGAGACCAGUUGCCUUUCAUAUAUUCUAGAAGAGAAGGAUGAGUGCUCUACAAGUAUAGAAAGAAGCCUUCCUCUUCCCACCGUCCCCAGACACCACAUAAUGGAAAAAGCAAGAAUUUUCUGCAUAAGCAAGGCCUUAAAAAAAAAAAAGCCAGCCUCUGAUGGGACUUCUUUCCUGCCAGAAAUCCCACUGGUCCACUGUCGCAAUUUUUACAAAAGGCCACGAUGAAAGAGUAAGGCCCAUUUUGAGCCCUUUGCUUCUGUAUUAUGUGAAACAUAACUUGUAUGUUUCACAUAUGUUCUUGGUAUCAGAAGAAUUGUUAGUUUUUGAACAUGUAAAAUCUACUAGGGUCUCUGACUGUUAAAGUAUAAUUUUGAUUAAGAAAAGAUUUGUUCCACUGCUUUGAUUAGACACAUAAAACUUUGAAAAGUUUUGAUGUUCUGUUUCCUGUUUUAAAAAAAUAUGUCCUCUCCUAUGAACUCUAACUAGAUGAGAGGAUUUUCCUCAGAGAAAAUUCAGCCCUGGGAAGAACCAUCUAUGGAGGUCAUAACCUAGAAAAUUCUUCAAGGGAAGUUGCAGUGAAUUAAAAGAGGGCGGAGUUAGAAAGUCCUGUUCUACCAAAUUUGUGCUAAUAGUUGCACCUUUCUUUCUUUCCCAGAAUGGUCACUGGAGAAAAUGUGUAAACCAACUGCAAACAAGUUUAUCCGUUGCCACCUUUCUUUUCCUUUAGUGACAGUUCAAUUCGUUAACCUGAAGGAGCUACUGUACCAUCAAGACUAGCUCCCAGCCCAGGGCUUCAGCAUAAAGCAGCUGCUCAGUUAAUUUUGGUGGAUCACGGGCAGAAACAAGUUACCUUUGGGAUGCAGAUUCUGAAUAGUCUGCCAUGAAAUGAUUAAAUGAAUGAGAGUGAUGAGGGGCUACUUAAUUGGACUAUGUAAAAUGGCUCCUUAAGCUUCGUGGACAAUUGAGUAAUUUCAGUUUCCUCUCUUCACUCUUGUUUACUUCCUGCUCUUCUAGCAUCAAGUGUUAGGUAUUCUGUUCUCUUACAAUGAGAAGAUUAAACAGCUGUAGUUUAAAUUAAAGCAUUAAUUUGGAGUGUUCUGUGGCUACAUUAAUUAUAUUUUCUACUAAGAUUAAAUUGCAGAUGGAUAUAAGCAGCAAUAUAUGUUUAUCCAGGGCAAACCAGAAUUCUGUUAACCAGCCAUCCUUGGUGACUUUUUAUUUAUAUAUAAAAACCUUUUUAAACUGAAAUAAUGUAACUUGAUUUUUCCCCCCAGUUAGGUAGAAGAAAAAAUAAUUGGAUGCAGAAAACAGUUGUAUGGAGCGUAUUUGCAUAGGUACAGGACUUGAGUGACAGAAAAUUCCUUUUAUUUUUUUCCCCAGUGGGAUUUAGCAAAAAGCAUGUGUUGAAAGUCUCUUGACUAAAUGGAUCAUAAUUAAAGACUUUGGGAUUUAUUUAUGGGUAUUUUAAUUAGAAACAUUAAGUUCACUCAGUGGUCCUUGUGAAAACUUUUUUCUAACUGCUUAUUUUAUAUCAAGUAAUAAAUAAAAUUUCUGUGGGUAUGAAGAUGAGUUUUAGGGCCGCCUAUUUCUCUAGGACCGCCCCCCCGCCCCCCGCCGCCGCUUCAGAGAGCUUUUCUCUUUCUUUCACCUAUUAAACUUCUGCUCUGGACCUCAAAAAAAAAAAAAGAGUUUUAGCUGUAACCACAUUGUAAUUCGUGCUGAAUAUAUGAAUGCUGCUGUUCACUGAAUAGUUAACUGGUUAUAUCCCUUGUUAAUUUGAAGUUUUCUUCCUUCGUUUUGGAAUGAUAGUUAUAAGGCAACAUGCAUUUUAGAAAAAUGCACUUGUUUGAACUUCUCAGAUCUAAUGUGACUCUGUGGGACUAGAUGUUAAGAAACCAUAUCUUUAACUGAACAUCAUCUAUGAUAUUCCAUCUCAUAACAUGUUCCAUGAGUUUUAUGGACAAUUUCUAAGAAAUCCAAAGUAGCAUGCAGUUUUAUCAACCUCUCUGCAUCCCCUUGGCACAAGGAAUAAUUUUUCUGUUAUUGAGGGGCAAAACAGAGGGGUAAAGGCACUCAUACAGUUAAAUGCCAGAUUAAGUCAGGCAUCCAAGUCACUCUGCUUUGGGUUGAUUCUCUGAGACUCAGCUGGCUGACUUCAAAAGGACGAAAUAGAUUUCAACAUUGGAAAAGAAUACAGUAUAGAAUAUAUGAUGGGUCUUGUUAGCUAUCUCUUAUUUUCUAAUCCAAAGAGCCUCCUAGUUGGAGGAAAAACUUGAACUACAUAAGUAUAUCAGCAAAUUUUCAUUAUAUUUUAUAAUUCUUUAUUGCAUUAUACGUGAAUAUAUUUAGCAGUGGUAGUACGUCUUGGAAAGUUUAAGAAUUUAGACAAAUAUGCUUUUUUUUUAAAAAAAAAUAGUUGAGUUUUAAAUAUGCUGUUUGGGUCCUUAUGAGCAUGUGGGAGAUAUAUAGGAGAAAGAGUUUGUUGCUGAUGUUAUAGAAUCACCAAUGCAGCAUUGCACUUUUGUUCUUUUCCAUUCAUUGUUCUUGCUUACAUGGAGCACUUGCAAAUAGGCUGGACGUCUCAGAGUUCUGAACAAUGCCCUUGGCUAACCGUUAGUCCUAAUUGCUGUGACUAAUGUGCUGUGUGACCUAAAGACGGUAACAUACUUAACCUUGGUUUUCUCAUCUGUAAAAUAGAAUUGAUGACCUCUACCAAGCCAAGGAUUUCAGUGAGGCACUCAAAAAUAAAAAUUAAAAAAUACAUUUGGGACAAACAUGAAAAAAAUUACUUUUUAGACUUAAGCAAUGCAUUUAAACCUGACGAAAAUGAAAGGAAUUGAAAUUGUUUAGCCACAGAAAAUAAAGACCAAGGACCAAUUUAAACAGUUGAAAAUUAUAUGAAGCAGUGUUUUAUGGAGAGUAGUAAUGAACUCUUCUUCACCUUUUUUGAGGCUGUCCAAAGAAGAAAUGAAGUUAGAUUAUUGCAGAAUUACAUAAGUUAGUAAGCAUGGACUGACCAGUUCUUUCUAAGACACAUACUUGAGUAUUUAUUCUCUUCAGUUGCAAUGAAGGUGACAGUGAAUUUGCUGAAUAGCUGUGUACAUGUUUCCCCAAAGAGACCACUGGAAUAAAGUUUUGUUUCUUGAGACAGUUUCCAUUGCAUUUAUAAGUCUUGUCCCUUGAAGGAUGUUUUCUGGUAAACACCUGUAUUCUUUUUACAUUAUAUAUCUUCAUUACCGUACAAGUUUGGUUGUGAGCCAUUCCAAAGUCUUUAGUAUGCUGUAUGGGUGUAUUCUAUACUUUAUACCUUAUUUGGAAGUCAUAAUAAUGUCAAAACUAUGCCUAGCCAUCCCCUUCCCUGCAGAGUCUCUUUUGCUUUGUCCACUUGGUGUGUAUAUUUUUUUUUUUUUUUUUUGAGACAGAGUUUUACUCGUCGCCCAAGCCGCAGUGCAGUGGCGCGAUCUCGGCUCGCUGCAACUUCUGCCUCCCGGGCCCAAGCGAUUCUCCUGCCUUAGCCCCCCAGGUAGCUGAGAUUACCGGUGCCCGCCACCACGCCCAGCUAAUUUUUGUAUUUUUAGUAGAGACAGGGUUUCACCAUGUUAGCCAGGCUGGUCUGGAACGCCUGACCUCAAACGGUCCAUCCGCUUCAGCCUCCCAAAGUGCUGGGAUUACAGGCGUGAGCCACCGCGCCCGUCCAUGUGUGUCUUUUUUAUUUUUUGUUUUUUGAGACGGAGUCUCGCUCUGUCGCCCAGGCUGGAGUGCAGUGGUGCGAUCUUGGCUCACUGCAAGCUCCGCCUCCUGGGUUCACGCCAUUCUCCUGCCUCAGCCUCCCGAGUAGCUGGGACUGCAGGCGCCUGCCACCACGUUGUGUGUCUUUUUAAAAGAUUUCCAGGACUUCUUUUUCCUUUACAAAUCCAAAAUUGCAGUAGCUUAAUAAAUAACAAAUAUUUUGGUUUUAUGAUUACUGUCAAAUAGCUCAUUAGUAAGAGAAAAAAAAAAAUGCUGAGCCUUAAGAGGGGAGAGGAAAGGCAGUCUUUCUGAAGCUGAAUCCUUUGCCUAAAUUGUCUUAGCAAUAAAUCUUGCCACCUAUUGGUAAAAAGGAAGAACUAAAACUAAAAGGUGUUUGCCGUUCUCACAGGUAGUUAGUAGUGUGAUCGAAAUAGAAUUCUUUCAGCGGUGCUUUUGGAUAAGGGGCUUGGAAAUAUGUGAUUUGAUAUGGAACUUUUCCCUGUGCUUUGAAUUUAUCAUGGCUCAUCUCUAAGUCAUAAUAGUUUUUUGAGUAGAGGAGGUAUGCUGCUCUCAUGGUCUCUCUUAAAAUUAUAUUUUUUGAGAUAGAAUUCCAUUUUAAUAGAUCAGUGGAUUUUAAUUGGACACAUUUUAGAGGCUUGAUUGAUUUUGAAAACAUUUUUCUUUUUUCUUUCUUUCUGUCUUUCUGCCUUUCUUUCCACCACGGCUAACUGCAGUCUGAACCUCCUGUGCUCAGUUGAUCCUCCCGCCUCAGCCUCCUGAGUAGCUGGGACUACAGGCGUGCGCCACCAUGCCUGGCUAAUUUUUCUGUAGAGAUGGGGUUUCACCAUGUUGCCUAGGCUGGUCUCAAGUGAUCUGUCUGCCUCAGCCUCCUAAAGGGCUAAAAUUAUAGGUGUGAGCCACUGCACGUGGCCUUUUUUUUUUUUUUUUCUUGAGACAGGGUCUUCCUCUGUCACUCAGGCUGGAGUAUAGUGGCAUCAACAUGGCUCACUGUAGCCUUGACAUCUUGGGGUCACCUGAUCCUCCUACCUCAGCCUCUGGUGUAGCUGGGACUACAGGCUGAAAACAUUUUUCUAACUCUGUUGUUAGUUUGGGCUUUCCUUCAUUCCAGCCUCUGAAAUCCAUUAUUUCCUGCCCAACGGGACAGGCCAGUGGUGACGUUGGCCUUUGGUGCCAGGGCCUGUUUUUCCAGAUCAUGGGCACCAUACAAAGAUAACUGCCCUAAACGGCAUCAUUGCCCCAGAGUCAUUGAAUGUCCUUAAGGUGCAUUUGAUAAAACAAAAACAGUUUUUUGUUUUGAAAAUUCUCAAGUAUUUCCAUACUGGGAAAAUGUUCUUUUUUUUUUUUUGACAGGGUCUUGCUCUGCUGCCCAGGCUGGAGUGCAGUGGCGGGAUCUCAAUUCACUGCAACCUCUGCAUCCUGGGUUCAAGCAAUUCUCCUGCCUCAGCUGGGACCACCGGCACAUGCCACUAAGCCCGGCUAAUUUUUGUAUUUUUAGUAGAGAUGGGGUUUUGCCAUGUUGGCCAGACUGGUCUUGAACUCUUGACCUCAAGAGUGACCCAUCUGCCUCGGCCUCCGAGAGUGCUGGGAUUACAGGCAUGAGCCACCAUGCCUGGCCAACAAUGUUCUUUUUAAUGGUGUUUUCCCCACUAUCUGGAUAGAUAUAUGAAUUCAGUUACUAAGAUGACUUAGAUUUAAAUAUAAAACACUAGCAUAGCAGUUUUUGAUUCUUAAUAUUAUCUUAAAUCCACCUCCCCUCAUUGUCCUCUGUAUCUAAACACCCUUCAAUUCUUGAGAAAAUUAAGAUUACCAAAGAUUAGUAAUCUAUUUGUGAUUGUGUGUGUUGGUGGACAUCCUAACAAAUUUAUGAAUAAAGCCAAUACUGUUUUGUUAGUGUCCUUAUUUUUUCUUUACGUCUGUUCAUAUUUGGAAUUCUAAGGCACUACCCAGAUAAUCAUUUGAUACCCUUUGUUGGCAUGACAUGUUUGGUCAAUUGUUUUGGCAAAAUUAUUUAUCCACCACUGGGAACUAAGCACUGUAACAACUAAAGAAAGAGGUCAUACAAGGGAAAUUGGAAGAACUAUAUGUUAUUUGUUUCAAUUUUUAUGUAGUACACCUAUAUAUGUGUGCAAAAAAAAUGUAAACUGUUACAAAGCAACAUAUUGAUGAAUUUAAAUGAGUAGAGCAUAAUAAAAGCAAAAACCAAACAGAAGAGUGGUUGGAGUGAGGCCAUAAUAAACCAAGAGAUAUUUUCUGAAGGAAGUGAACAUGUUUGCAUUUUCCAGCAUACUGCUAUGGAUGUCAGCGUUAGGCUAAUACAUAGUAUUGCAGCGUGAUUCAAAAAGGUGAGAUAGAGGGGAAAUAAGAUAGCUUCAUAAAUAUUACCAAGGAAUUUAAGACAUGAGCAUUUUAUGUAGGGAGGUUGAAAUGCAUUGUUAUAAUCAGGCUGUGUAAUUUCCUUCUGUCAAGACCUACCCAUUUACCAGUAAUGAUACCUUCUUUCUCUUCUAUUUUUGUCUCUUCCUUUAGGAAAAGGAAUAUAUGCUUACUCAUUAUUUAAAAUUCAGAGUCAUUUUCCUGUUCCAGUUGGUUUUGUUCCUGGAACCACCAAAGAAGAGUAGAAUUAGGUGCAUGUGAAACUUUUGUUUCUGCUUUUUCUACUCAAUCAACUUUUAUCCCUUUUUAAUUUUUACUCUCUCAACCAUCAGUUCUAUAUCAUGGUAUCUCUUCUUGGUCUUUUUGUAUUAUAUUUCCAUAAAACCAGAUGUACGGGGUUGUUAAAAUACUGCCUGGACAUAUUAUCUACCCUGCACUAAGUGGUCCUAUCACAAAAUCCAGUUAAACACACAUUGAAGUAUUUAAAUUGUUUCUUUUUUAAAUAACAUCAUAUUGGGCAUUGGACUUCUUAACUAAACUAUUUCUUUCACUAAAUGACAUUGGUUAAUUCAACAAGCCAUUGUAGGAAUUCUGUUAACCCAGUAGCUUCUACUACUAUGUUACUAUGGUAAUGACUUAGCUUCCCAUAAAGCUGCAUUUAAAUAGGUGUUUAUAGUCACCAAUUACCAGGUAUUUCAAGUACUCUUUGAAAGGGGCCUGCUUGUGGUGGGGUGGGGGGCGUUAACAUAGAUACUUUCUCAGUCACGUAGCCAUUUGAAGUUUUUCAGGUAGAAGACAGUUGAUAGACUAUUUGGUGAGCAAAUGAAUAACUGGAUGAAUACCCAUCUGGGAACCCCUAAAGAACUGAAGAUAGUUCCCUGGCCAUCACUGUUCACAGUCAUCUAUUAUGUGCUUACUCUAUGCCAAGUGUUGGGCUGGAUUCUGGGGUCACCAAAGGGAAGAGAAAAUUUUCACUGCCUUGAGGGUAGCUAAAAACUUAAUGGAGGGAAGCUGAGAGCAUGAGCGAGCGUGCCACCCCAGCUGGGUGAGCGGCACACCUUGGGAACAGCUGGGAGACCCCCAGUGGUGUGUGUCUUCCUUCGCCCUUAGCACUUGCUCCUCUCCAGCUCACUGUGUUUCUUUUCUCUCUGGGGUCUAAGGAGCUUAGGCUUCACUGCCUGCUCCUCAGAUUGUGGGAGCAGGAGCAGAGAGUGGGUGCCUGCCACGGGACAGGGGGUCCUAGAGACAGGCCCCAGCAUGGGAAGGCAGUGGAAACCCAUGCAUUGCUCUCUGGCAUUGCCACACGUCUUCUGCUGCCUGCCUUCCAGCCCUUUGCUUUUCCCCAGCUCCGUCAGCUCCUUGCCUCUGACAUCAGUGAUGAAAGUCAGGCGUGGGGGGAUUAGAUUAUUUCCAUUGGCCUUGAUAGACUUAGACAUAUAAUAGAAGCUAUGAUAAGUGAGUUAGUUUUCCAUGUUUGUUUACUGAAGUUUAUAUUACCCUUUAUGUCACCAAAACAUGCCCGUUUGCAGUCAUUGCCAAUGUAGUCAUGCAAAAUCACUUGAGUGAAAUAGACUUUGGGGAUCUAAUCUCAGGACCUAACCACCAUUUAUAAAGCUUUUUUGGGGAAAAUGUGUUCUGGAUUUCGCACAGCCAGCUUACAAAUGAGCUUUGGAAACACAAUCCACAUGUAAGUUGGAGACUUCCUAUUAUUAGCAUUCAGCCCUGCGAGGAGAGCCCUUGCUUUGUUAGCAGGCCUAUGUGUCCUCAGCCCUAAGUUCCUAAAACCAGCACUACUUGAGGAGCUUGAAUUGGUGCUCUUGGAGUUCUUUAGAUUAGUUAUGAGACUUCAGAACCUGCUUACCAGCAGUACUGAGCUCAAGAGGAAGCCUAAUUCAUAUCCUUCAGAAGAUAAUUUUAAGAGAGUGUGUAUGUUUUCGUUUUGUGAACAAAGGAAAGUUAAUCUGGUGCUCCGUGUCUGUUUUGUAAUUCCCCAAGGGAGAAGGAAAGGGAGGGAAAUGAUUGAUUUCCAGAUAGGAUAAAAACCAGUCAGCACACAAUGGGUUACUGCCACCGCUUUCUGAUAAGGAUCCUACUUCAACUAUCUGAAGAGAUUCUUCAAGGUGGAGGAUACAGUGGUUAUAUUAGUUACUCUCACCCUUGUUAUUAUGGAAGGUAAAAUUCCUGGAUCCUAGAUUUAAUUUUAAAAUAGUAAUUUAAUAAUGUCUGGUGGAAACCUCUUAAAAAAAACACUUUGCAGCACAUCUCUGGUAGCCCUGUGCUUGAGAUGACUUUUAGGCUGCCAGUUCAGAAGAUGGAAGAUAUAAACUGUGUUGAUGAGUUGGUUUUUCAGUGGACCCUGUUAGGUUCCUUUUUUAAAAAAAUAAUAAUUUUUAUAAUGAGUAUGUCUUCGUGAGCCCUCACAACCCUUGAAGUUUUUACUUGUUUGGCAGAACUAAGGGCACUGAACGUUUGUAAGCCGUUCACUAACACUUACAGGAAGGGCAUAAAAGGGUGCUCAAGUCAGUCUGUAGGUGGUGGGGGCGGGGUGGAAAGAGGGGAUUCCUGUAGGCCUGGAUGAAUCAGCCACUGAUUUCUGAUGGUAGCCCCAGCUGCAAAAAAGUAGGAAGCUUUUUUUAUGGACAGAACUACAACUCCUUUCUUUCAAGUUUUUCAGCCUUUUCACACUUUUCCAUUCUUCAGACUUUGCAAGUUUUUAAACAAAAUGUUUGUAUUUCCCCAAAGGAAAUCACACAGUUGACUGCAUUAUGAGAGGGAAAGGAGCAAACUCUGUCUCAUCUGAGGAGGGGCUCAGAUCAGGAGUUGUGUAGGGCCCUCACCCGGUUGGGGGUGGUGGAGCCUUGGCUGUGUGCAGGAGUGACUGUUCUUGGAGAUGUUCUGGUUGGAUCAUGAGUUUGGGCUUGGAAAGCACUGCCUCAAGUUCAUCAGCAGGAAUGAGGUAGAAUUCACUACUUGCUGUCUUAAGACCUUUCUGUCUGCCAAGUGUUUGAGCAAUCCCUCACAUCUCCCCCUUGAACUAAAGAGCAACAACUGGUCAAGAGCCCAGCAGGGAUGAAAAAGGUUGGCCCCUUGCAUCCUUCAUCUGCUGUUUAGACUAAGGGCCGCAUUGUAGACCACUCUCGGCCAUGCUGUCCUGAACCCGAGGAUCAGCAGAAUUACAGGCCCAAUUUCAGGCAGACGUGAGCUUGCAUCUGAUGACAGCUUUGACUCUCCCGGAUCUUGCAGAGCAGUUUGCCCCUCCUGACAUUGCCCCGCCUCUUCUUAUCAAGCUCGUGGAAGCCAUUGAAAAGAAAGGUCUGGAAUGUUCAACUCUAUACAGAACACAGAGCUCCAGCAACCUGGCAGAAUUACGACAGCUUCUUGAUUGUGAUACACCCUCCGUGGACUUGGAAAUGAUCGAUGUGCACGUUUUGGCUGACGCUUUCAAACGCUAUCUCCUGGACUUACCAAAUCCUGUCAUUCCAGCAGCCGUUUACAGUGAAAUGAUUUCUUUAGCUCCAGAAGUACAAAGCUCCGAAGAAUAUAUUCAGCUAUUGAAGAAGCUUAUUAGGUCGCCUAGCAUACCUCAUCAGUAUUGGCUUACGCUUCAGUAUUUGUUAAAACAUUUCUUCAAGCUCUCUCAAACCUCCAGCAAAAAUCUGUUGAAUGCAAGAGUACUCUCUGAAAUUUUCAGCCCUAUGCUUUUCAGAUUCUCAGCAGCCAGCUCUGAUAAUACUGAAAACCUCAUAAAAGUUAUAGAAAUUUUAAUCUCAACUGAAUGGAAUGAACGACAGCCUGCACCAGCACUGCCUCCUAAACCACCAAAACCUACUACUGUAGCCAACAACGGUAUGAAUAACAAUAUGUCCUUACAAGAUGCUGAAUGGUACUGGGGAGAUAUCUCGAGGGAAGAAGUGAAUGAAAAACUUCGAGAUACAGCAGACGGGACCUUUUUGGUACGAGAUGCGUCUACUAAAAUGCAUGGUGAUUAUACUCUUACACUAAGGAAAGGGGGAAAUAACAAAUUAAUCAAAAUAUUUCAUCGAGAUGGGAAAUAUGGCUUCUCUGACCCAUUAACCUUCAGUUCUGUGGUUGAAUUAAUAAACCACUACCGGAAUGAAUCUCUAGCUCAGUAUAAUCCCAAAUUGGAUGUGAAAUUACUUUAUCCAGUAUCCAAAUACCAACAGGAUCAAGUUGUCAAAGAAGAUAAUAUUGAAGCUGUAGGGAAAAAAUUACAUGAAUAUAACACUCAGUUUCAAGAAAAAAGUCGAGAAUAUGAUAGAUUAUAUGAAGAAUAUACCCGCACAUCCCAGGAAAUCCAAAUGAAAAGGACAGCUAUUGAAGCAUUUAAUGAAACCAUAAAAAUAUUUGAAGAACAGUGCCAGACCCAAGAGCGGUACAGCAAAGAAUACAUAGAAAAGUUUAAACGUGAAGGCAAUGAGAAAGAAAUACAAAGGAUUAUGCAUAAUUAUGAUAAGUUGAAGUCUCGAAUCAGUGAAAUUAUUGACAGUAGAAGAAGAUUGGAAGAAGACUUGAAGAAGCAGGCAGCUGAGUAUCGAGAAAUUGACAAACGUAUGAACAGCAUUAAACCAGACCUUAUCCAGCUGAGAAAGACGAGAGACCAAUACUUGAUGUGGUUGACUCAAAAAGGUGUUCGGCAAAAGAAGUUGAACGAGUGGUUGGGCAAUGAAAACACUGAAGACCAAUAUUCACUGGUGGAAGAUGAUGAAGAUUUGCCCCAUCAUGAUGAGAAGACAUGGAAUGUUGGAAGCAGCAACCGAAACAAAGCUGAAAACCUGUUGCGAGGGAAGCGAGAUGGCACUUUUCUUGUCCGGGAGAGCAGUAAACAGGGCUGCUAUGCCUGCUCUGUAGUGGUGGACGGCGAAGUAAAGCAUUGUGUCAUAAACAAAACAGCAACUGGCUAUGGCUUUGCCGAGCCCUAUAACUUGUACAGCUCUCUGAAAGAACUGGUGCUACAUUACCAACACACCUCCCUUGUGCAGCACAACGACUCCCUCAAUGUCACACUAGCCUACCCAGUAUAUGCACAGCAGAGGCGAUGAAGCGCUUACUCUUUGAUCCUUCUCCUGAAGUUCAGCCACCCUGAGGCCUCUGGAAAGCAAAGGGCUCCUCUCCAGUCUGAUCUGUGAAUUGAGCUGCAGAAACGAAGCCAUCUUUCUUUGGAUGGGACUAGAGCUUUCUUUCACAAAAAAGAAGUAGGGGAAGACAUGCAGCCUAAGGCUGUAUGAUGACCACACGUUCCUAAGCUGGAGUGCUUAUCCCUUCUUUUUCUUUUUUUCUUUGGUUUAAUUUAAAGCCACAACCACAUACAACACAAAGAGAAAAAGAAAUGCAAAAAUCUCUGCGUGCAGGGACAAAGAGGCCUUUAACCAUGGUGCUUGUUAAUGCUUUCUGAAGCUUUACCAGCUGAAAGUUGGGACUCUGGAGAGCGGAGGAGAGAGAGGCAGAAGAACCCUGGCCUGAGAAGGUUUGGUCCAGCCUGGUUUAGCCUGGAUGUUGCUGUGCACGGUGGACCCAGACACAUCGCACUGUGGAUUAUUUCAUUUUGUAACAAAUGAACGAUAUGUAGCAGAAAGGCACGUCCACUCACAAGGGACGCUUUGGGAGAAUGUCAGUUCAUGUAUGUUCAGAAGAAAUUCUGUCAUAGAAAGUGCCAGAAAGUGUUUAACUUGUCAAAAAACAAAAACCCAGCAACAGAAAAAUGGAGUUUGGAAAACAGGACUUAAAAUGACAUUCAGUAUAUAAAAUAUGUACAUAAUAUUGGAUGACUAACUAUCAAAUAGAUGGAUUUGUAUCAAUACCAAAUAGCUUCUGUUUUGUUUUGCUGAAGGCUAAAUUCACAGCGCUAUGCAAUUCUUAAUUUUCAUUAAGUUGUUAUUUCAGUUUUAAAUGUACCUUCAGAAUAAGCUUCCCCACCCCAGUUUUUGUUGCUUGAAAAUAUUGUUGUCCCGGAUUUUUGUUAAUAUUCAUUUUUGUUAUCCUUUUUUAAAAGUAAAUGUACAGGAUGCCAGUAAAAAAAAAAAAUGGCUUCAGAAUUAAAACUAUGAAAUAUUUUACAGUUUUUCUUGUACAGAGUACUUGGCUGUUAGCCCAAGGUUAAAAAGUUCAUAACAGAUUUUUUUUGGACUGUUUUGUUGGGCAGUGCCUGAUAAGCUUCAAAGCUGCUUUAUUCAAUAAAAAAAAGAAAUGAAAAAGAUAUAUGAAUAUGACAAAGUAUUGCUGAGUCCAACAAUGUUGUUUUAAGACUCUUAAAAUACGGUACCUGGCAAUGUUUAUUUCAUAAAGAAUUGUGAACUUCUUGAAUCUAGGGAGGGGGAAUGUAGUGAAGGGAUGUAUCAAGUGGGGUGGUGGGAGGGGGAGGCAAGGUUAUAUGCACUUUCUCAUGAUUUACAGAGAAGUGAAUAACUGCAAAGUGAAGUUGCUUCUUCUACUUCAGUCUUCUCUCACUUUGAUUUGCUAGUUGUUAUCAAUUAAUGACAAUUACAAACCUACUGUAUCUCUAAUACAGUGUGACUGGUCAGGUAUUUCAGUUCUUAGGAAGGAAGUGCCAAGUUUGUUUUUGGGUUCCUGGAACAGCGCUCACCUUUGUUUAGAACACUGGUUUAAAGGGAUAAUCAUCUCUGUCACAUUAGACUAUCCAUCAUGACCAGCAAAUACUCAUUUUAGGAAAAAAAAAAGCAUGAUCUGAAAAAUACUUUUGGUGGUAUGUUGGUUACCCUCCUAGCUUUCCAUUUGGUUUAGAACAUAAAGCAAAUAGACACAGUCAUACUGUCACUGCUCUGGACUGUGUGGAGCUCGCUAAAGUCAUGGUCAUUGCAGGAAUCCAAGUGGCAGUCCUUCUCAUUCAUUCUAAUCAUUGUAUGUGCUUCACUACGGGGGGGAGAAGGAAACGUUAGCAUCAUGUUUCCCAUUUAGGGCAGGAGUGAGAGGUCUCUCUUCCUGAUUUAGAUAUGCAAAAGCUGGUAUGUUCAGUAGGAACUGUACAUGUGUUGGGAGGCAUAAAGACUAAUUAGCAACCAUAAUAUGGUCACUACCCUAAUAGACUAAAUGAAAUCUUGCAAUUUCAAAUUACUCUUUCUCCAUAUUAGAUUUACCCACAGCUAUAUUUCUGUUUAAGUACUAGGGUGAGGGUUUUCUGUUACUUUGUUUUUUAAUGUUGUUCCUUUUGAAAGAAUCAGUCUUGCAGCUGAGUGAAAAAUCUGUGGAAUGUAUUAUUUGUCCUCUUUACAUGAAACUACUCAUACUUAAGCAAAAGUCAGUCUUAUAGCAAGACUGUUAGCCCUCAAACUUGACUCUACUGAUCUGACCAUUUCCCUCUCAUCGCCAGACAACUGACGAUUUCCCUGGUUUUAGUCUGCGUCUCUGCUUUAAAGUUAUUGUGAUAUCCUUCUAGAUCAUACACAAGUCUAACAGUUAAUUAGUUAACAGUUUUUAAACUAGGUUUGUGGGUAUUUUUUUGGUAGCACAUGUAUGCUAUUACAUACAAAUUUUUAUUUCUAAAAUAUAAGAUCUGAGAUUGAAUAUUUUCAUUAAAAGCUACAGUUUUGUGAAUCUUUGUGCUUCAACAUUCUUUGCAAGAUGAUACGGUAUUUAGGCAUUUGCCUUAUUUUUGCAUCUCACAAACAUAAGUGCAAUAGAUCUUUUCAUUGAACAGCAAAGUAGGAUUCAUCAUUCCAUAUGACUUGAGUUACACCAGACCUGUUCUGCCCAAUGCCUUUUUGAUUACAGUGUAGCUUGCCCACCGCAUUUGUCGUUUUAGAUACUUUGCUAGCCGGCCACUUUGGAUUUCAUCAGACAGUCCUAACAAUAUUGUCUGAACGGCUGAAUAUGAAUAGAUACAGCAGAGGCACUCCUGAUAUAUGAUUUUUAUCCAUGCGUCAGUUUUUCCCACCCAGUGUAGCAUCCUAAAGAUAAAGCCAGAAGCUAAGCUGCAGUGAGGCUGUGAUUGGGCGUAGAAGUGGGAGCAUUGGGACCUCACAUUACACACACGAGAGAUCAUAACCAUGUGAAAAGGCAAAAAGCAUGUGUUUGCAACAUCUGAUAACUUCAUGGCCUUUGAUAAAUGUAUAUAUGUAUAUGUGCAUGGACUGUGUUUCCAGUACACCUUUCAGCCAAAACAGAUCCACAGUAGUUGUUGAGUUCAAGUACAUAAAGUACAUAACAAGCGAACGUCUAGUACAAUUCUUACUUAUGUGUAUGGGAUUUUUCCCUUUGAGGUUGCUUUGUUUUGUCUUACAAAGGUGAAAAUUGUUUGUAAGUGAAGUGAGAAGUUCAUAUUUCUUUGGCUUUUUUGUGUUUUUAAAAGUUACUCCUUUUAGGGAGCUGGUCUGAUGACUUGCUUAGCUUGGAAAUCCUUGUUUUCAGUGUGUCGAGUCAAAAUGUGUUUAUGUGAGCUGUCACUGUGGGGAACCAAUUGCUUUGUCAUAUAGCUGGUUAUGAACUAGUAACAUGUUUGGGAAGUCCUACUGAUGUUCCUUUGGAAGAAAAAAUCUGCUGGUUUUAACAACUGUGCUUUUGCUAUGUAUGGUAUCCAAGUUAGUUGAAACGCAGACACUGAGAUCUGUUUGAGUUUAGGGUCAUUUUUAGAAAGGGGCAGUUUAAAGCACAAUGUCUCACAUGGGACAAAGUUCCAAAAUGCCAAAUUCUUAUUUUUUAAAAAGCUAGUUCUAUAAAAUACUGGUAUUAUGGGUGGGGAGGAAAUAGAAUUGAGUCAAUUGGAAAGACUAUCCAACUUAACAUGAAACUUGUCACCAUGAGAUAGCAUUAGCUGCCCAGGAUGCUGCUAUAUAUAUAUAUAUAUAUAUAUAUGUGUGUGUGUGUGUGUGUGUGUGUGUAUAUAUAUAUAUAUAUAUAUAUAUAUAUAUAUAUAUAUAUGUGUGUGUAUAUAUAUAUAUAUGUGUAUAUAUAUAUGUAUAUACAUAUAUGUAUAUAUAUGCACAUAUAUAUAUGUAUUUAAAAAAAUCAAAACAAAAAAAAACUCAUUUAUACCUGUGUAUUUUUUAAAGCUACAAUCUGUUCAAUGUUUUUAAAAAUCUGUUUAUAUGACAUUGUUAAAAUAAAGUUGGUCUUUUGACGAGAGGGAGGAUGUCACGGUCAGUUGUAACUUUGCCUUCACAAGGCAACUGGGGUGGGGGGUGGGGGUAGUGUGCCUCCUUGACAUUUCGUUCAAGUUAUAGAUUCAAUGGAGCUAUGUCUUGUUUUAAGUUGCUUUAAUGCAUUGUAUUAGAUCUUCAAACAGAAUAAAGGUUGUUUUGAAACUGAA